GGGAGCUGGGAAGCCCGGCGCGCGUCGUUUGCUGGGGCUGUUUGUGCGUUGCUGCUGUGCUACCGCGUUGCGUUUUCUAGGCAUUUACUUACACGCUUUGUGGUUUACGCUCUCAUAACCUUGUGGUUUUAUAGUCCUUAAAUUAUUGUAGCGCACGUUACUUAAAUCCAGAAGCAGAUGUGUACCCCAGCAAGAGAUAAAAUGACGCUCAGAGUCAGUAGAUCCAGACCGUGCCUGAGAUCCUGAAUCCUGUUUCCUACCCACUAUUCAGCCAUUGGGUCACAAGCGAUGAAAAGAGCACCUUGAAGACAGAUUUCCCCACGCAGACGCUGUGUGUCACAGGGGGAAUGGGCAGCGUCACUUUUUACAUCCAGUCAUAUUGUAUGAAAUUGCAACAAAUUCAAAAAGAUGCCAUCGUGGGAGUGUGAAGACACUAUUGUAAUAGCAUGGCUAGGAAGGAAACACAGCUAAUUAUUAAGAUGAAUCAUUUAGCAAGGUCCUGACCAGCUCUAAAGAUGGGUCAGCUGCUGUAUUUCCAAGAACCCCAUGACUUCCAGGGCCCCUUGUUCCCAGGAAGGCCCCGCACCCCAGUCGUCCCGUGCAUAACCUCACGGGCCAGCACCUGGUAGCUGCUGGAAGGCUUCUGGGGGAUGCCUGGGCCCCUCCAGCCCUACCUCUAGUCCUGCCACUUUACAACUGAGCACCUCCCGCUGCUGCCUGCUGAACCCUUCAGAGUCCUUGCCACAGGCCCUAUUUACUUUUUCCUGAGAAGAUUUGUGGUCUGCAUUAUGUCUGGAGCCAGAAGUAAGCUUGCUCUUUUCCUCUGCGGCUGUUACGUGGUUGCCCUGGGAGCCCACACCGGGGAGGAGAGCGUGGCUGACCAUCACGAGGCUGAAUAUUAUGUGGCUGCCGUGUAUGAGCAUCCAUCCAUCCUGAGUCUGAACCCUCUGGCUCUCAUCAGCCGCCAAGAGGCCUUGGAGCUCAUGAACCAGAACCUUGACAUCUAUGAACAGCAAGUGAUGACUGCAGCCCAAAAGGAUGUACAGAUUAUAGUGUUUCCAGAAGAUGGCAUUCAUGGAUUCAACUUUACAAGAACAUCCAUUUAUCCAUUUUUGGACUUCAUGCCGUCUCCCCAGGUGGUCAGGUGGAACCCAUGCCUGGAGCCUCACCGCUUCAAUGACACAGAGGUGCUCCAGCGCCUGAGUUGUAUGGCCAUCAGGGGAGAUAUGUUCUUGGUGGCCAAUCUUGGGACAAAGGAGCCUUGUCAUAGCAGUGACCCAAGGUGCCCAAAAGAUGGGAGAUACCAGUUCAACACAAAUGUCGUGUUCAGCAAUAAUGGAACCCUUGUUGACCGCUACCGUAAACACAACCUCUACUUUGAGGCAGCAUUCGAUGUUCCUCUUAAAGUGGAUCUCAUCACCUUUGAUACCCCCUUUGCUGGCAGGUUUGGCAUCUUCACAUGCUUUGAUAUAUUGUUCUUUGACCCUGCCAUCAGAGUCCUCAGAGACUACAAGGUGAAGCAUGUUGUGUACCCAACUGCCUGGAUGAACCAGCUCCCACUCUUGGCAGCAAUUGAGAUUCAGAAAGCUUUUGCUGUUGCCUUUGGCAUCAACGUUCUGGCAGCUAAUGUCCACCACCCAGUUCUGGGGAUGACAGGAAGUGGCAUACACACCCCUCUGGAGUCCUUUUGGUACCAUGACAUGGAAAAUCCCAAAAGUCACCUUAUAAUUGCCCAGGUGGCCAAAAAUCCAGUGGGUCUCAUUGGUGCAGAGAAUGCAACAGGUGAAACGGACCCAUCCCAUAGUAAGUUUUUAAAAAUUUUGUCAGGCGAUCCGUACUGUGAGAAGGAUGCUCAGGAAGUCCACUGUGAUGAGGCCACCAAGUGGAACGUGAAUGCUCCUCCCACAUUUCACUCUGAGAUGAUGUAUGACAAUUUCACCCUGGUCCCUGUCUGGGGAAAGGAAGGCUAUCUCCACGUCUGUUCCAAUGGCCUCUGCUGUUAUUUACUUUACGAGAGGCCCACCUUAUCCAAAGAGCUGUAUGCCCUGGGGGUCUUUGAUGGGCUUCACACAGUACAUGGCACUUACUACAUCCAAGUGUGUGCCCUGGUCAGGUGUGGGGGUCUUGGCUUCGACACCUGUGGACAGGAAAUCACAGAGGCCACGGGGAUAUUUGAGUUUCACCUGUGGGGCAACUUCAGUACUUCCUAUAUCUUUCCUUUGUUUCUGACCUCAGGGAUGACCCUAGAAGUCCCUGACCAGCUUGGCUGGGAGAAUGACCACUAUUUCCUGAGGAAAAGUAGGCUGUCCUCUGGGCUGGUGACGGCGGCUCUCUAUGGGCGCUUGUAUGAGAGGGACUAGGAAAAGUGUGUGGUCUGUGGGGCGGACUCUGGCCAUCAUGUUGACAGCCUUGCACUUCCACAGGCUACAAGCCCUGGGACCAUCUUUCUGCCUUAAGGGCAGGAGCCCACUUCUGUGGCACCAGAUUCCACCCUGGGAACUGUGGAAAAAGUAGGAGAGGCAGAUUCCCUCAGUGUCUUCCUCUUAAACCUCAAUCAUCGAGACAUUAGGGGGUAUUUUCUGUUCACAUUUAUCUUUUUCAAGCCACAUCUUCCUCUAACAAAUCUCUCAGUAUGCGAUUGGUCUCAAGCUAAAACAAAAAUAAAUGUCAGUUUAUAUUUUACACAUCCACAAAGCAGUGGCUUGGGGUUUUUUUUUUUUUUUUUAUCUUGUUGAUCAAGUGACACCCAGGACAUGUAAAUAUUUCAUAAGCCUUAAACAUUUCCUGAGGUAAGAAACAAGCUCUCAAAGCAAAAGCUCAAUUAGAAAUGGCCCUUGUGGGGAACCUUCCCAUUCUGGUCGACCAGAACUCUAGCCAGAUGAAAUGGCAAUGCUAGCGCCACCAGCAACGUCAGAAACGUAGACCUUAAAGCGGCUUUUAAAAAUAGAAAAGAAGCGUUCCUCACAUCUGCCAGUAAUGGAAUUUUCUGUCAGUAAAUGGAAUGUGUAGGCAGGACCUGGAAUAACUGGAGAGAGUGCAACGCUUCGGGGUGAAGGGCGGGUGGGGACUGGAAAUGUUGAGACGGGGGCAGCCAUGGGAAGGUAUGAGUAAUAGAAUUCUUUCUGUACGACACAGCUCAUCCAGGGAUUCCAGGGACCUUAAUAAAUCACGGUAGCUUUGGGCAAGAGUUGGGCACGUUGCCCGACUGUGCAGGAUGGAUUGAUGCUGGUAUAAUUUGAUCUGGAGCCCUAUAGAGGAUCUCGUUGCUUUGCAGCGAUGCCUGGCACCCCAUAGAGAUAAGUUGCAGGGACUGCCGUGAAGGGCAUGAAGGGUGGCCCACUUUAGUCAUGCAUUUAUUCAAUCACCCAACAGGCACAGAGCAGGAGCUUCCCAUGUUAGGAAUUCCAGAUGCAAAAUUAUCAGACUCAAUAUGGUGAAGACAUUUUUAGGCCACUGAUUUCUGUGUAAUUUGUGUCCAAUAUUUCAAAGCCAUUUAAAAAAGGAUUUUGACUGCAUGCCUAGUAGCUGUUUCAGAUCAUUUUUUAAGUACAGAAUGGAUAAUUAGUCUUCAGUGAUUUGCCUCUUAAAUGUGGCCAUUUAGUUUGAACUCCUUUUUAGUUAUUUUAAACAGUAUAUGCUUAAACAUCACACGAUUUUAUAAAGCAAGAAAAAUGAAAUGAUCUCCCUAUUCCCCCACGGUGUAGGCCUCCAGAUCCUUUUCUGGCUUUUAGGCAGGACAAUUAACAAUGUGGAUUCUGCAGUCAGACUGAUGGGGUUUCCAUGCAUGGCCUCACCAUUAACUCCUCACUGGGGAGACCUUGGGCCUCGGUUUUUUAUUCAUAGAAUGCAUGUUGAAUAAACCAUGUGGGAAAAAGCAGAGCCAGCACCAGCCCCUGCUGACUCACUGAUCCCUCGGAAAGGUCUGGGAUGAGUCAAGUCUUCAGGGAAUAAGCAGCAAGGACUUGGAAUUCCUGAGCAAGCCUUGGGUUCCCCACGCCCUAGGAAGUCCCUCUGGAAGGGGAGCAGGACCUCUCCCACCAGAUGACGGAGUUCGCUUUCUCGCCCAGCGCAGCUCCCACCAGGCGUGAGCUGGCAGUCCAGAAGCGGCCCCAGAUGUGGCUACCCACCGCCCAGUCUGCUUCCCUGCCUCAAACCCCAGGGAGACAGAAAUUACCUAAAAAUGCAUAUCAUUGCCUUAUGCCAAGAUGAUUCAAAUAAGCCUGAGAAAGAGAGGCCAGCGCUAAAUACAGACUUGGCAGAACUACUUCACCCAGUAAACAUCUAAUCAGCACCUGCAGGAUCCUCAUUCUGCCCUUCUGGGCAGAGCACCACGAACUUUCCCUGAGUUAUUUUCUACCAACAAUUUAGAAUGAAUUGCUCGUGAAGUAGAAAUGAGGGGAAAAGCAACUAAUGGUGGUAGAACAAAGUAAUUUUUACAAUUAAAAGAAGUAGCUGCCAGAUGACAGAACAAAGUAGAGGACGGGAAAAUAAAUCAUUUUCAGGGAAAAAAUAUAUCUAUGACUAAUGGUUGUGAUUAUGUUUUUGUCGAUUGUGAUCCUGAAACUCAGGAAGCAAAUGGCAAUCUUGACCACAACAUGGAGACAGGAAAUCAAAUGCAUUUUUGGCUAAACCAGACUUGGGGGAAGUGGCUUGGUUUGCGUGGUUUCUCAUGUAGGUGCAGCUGUGCUUUUCUGUGGUUUUUCUCACACGGGAAGUGAGAGGCACAGUGAGCUGUAUUCACACUGGAUUUAAAAGCCCUGUUCUUAGAGAGGAAAAAACCAGGCCUCCUCACAGACUGCCAAGUCCCAGAGCCCACCAUGUCUGCUCUCAAGACACAGGCCUGUCCAGAGCCCCUGCUGAGGGAAACCCACCCAGGCCACUUUUCCCCACAGGUGGCCCUGCUUGGUACCUGUGCCCCCACCCCCCAGCCAUGGUAUAUUGAACCAGGAGGAGGCACCCAGCCCAAGGCCAGCCAAUCAGAGCACUGGCUAGUAGCCCAGGAGGUGUCCCUGCACAGAAGAUCUCCUCAGAGAGGACCGAUGGUGAGUCGGCCGCUCUUGAUUCUCAAUGAAACUCAGAACCGCUCAAGUGAAAUGACCACUCAAAGAACAAUUUCUCAACAAAGUGGAUUUAUAUAGGACAAAAUAGGCAUAAAAGUAUGAAAUGUUUUGUGCACAAAGGCCUAGAUUUGAGACAAGAGCUGAUGUGGCCUGAAGAUCUGUGAGUGGGACUGCUUGGGAGGCCAUGUUCCUUCUCAGGCCAGAGAAAGGUCCUGGUCUCCUGGCUUCAGUCUUUCAUUCCCUAACCUCCCUUUGAAUGUUAGUUACCUAUUCCCACAUAACAAAGUGCCCCAAAACUUAAUGGCAUAAAACAAGCAUGGACAUUGUUAGUUCACCCAGUUCUGUGGGGCAGGAAAGCGGGUCUCUCAUGAGGCUACAGUCAAGAUGUCAGCCGAGGUGACAGUGAAGAUAUCAACCAAGGCUGCAGCCGGUUGAAGGCCUCACUGGAUUUGGAGAAUAUUAUUGAUUAAAUUGCGUCUUCCCCAAAAAAGAUACGUUGUAGUCCUAACCCCCAAUAGCUCAGAAUGUGGCCUUAUUUGGAAAUAGGGUCUUUGCAGAUGCAAUGAAGAUAUAAGUUAAAAUGAGAUCACACUAGAGUAACUGGGCCCUUAAUCCAAUAUGACAUGUCCUUAUCAGAAGAGGAGAAGACACACACACAGGGAGAAGAUGACCAUGUGACAACAGGGGCAGAGAUCACAGGGAUGCCUCUACUAGACAAGGCACACCAGAAAUUGCUUGCCAACAAACACCAGAAAUUAGAAGAGGCAAGAAACAACUCCCCACACACAACCCACCCCUGCAGGUUUCAGAAGAAGCAUGGCUCUGCCAACACCUUGAUUUUGGAUUUCCAGCUUCCACAACUAUGAGACAAUAAGUUUCUGUUGUUUGAAGCCACCCAGUUCAGGGUACUUUGAUAUGGCAGACCUAGGAAACAAAUACAGAGGAUCACUUGCAAAAUGGCCCAUUCACACAGCUGGCACGUUGGUGCUGGCUGCUAGCAAAAGGUCUCAGCUCCUCACCACUUGGGUCUUUCCAUAGGGAUAGCUGAGUGUCCUCAUGAUGUGGCCCCUGGCUUCCCCUGAAGCAAAUGAUCCAAGAGAGCACAGGUGGAGCCAUGAUGUCUUUUAUUAACUAGUCUCAGAAGUCACACUGCAUCAUUUGGCACCAUCUUAUUGAGUUACACAGGUCAGCCCUGCUCCCUAUGGAAAGAGACAGAGGGUGUUAGAUGCCCAGAGGUGAACCUCAUUGGGUACCAUCCUGCAGGUGGGCUGCCACUCUGCUCAAUCCAAAUCACAGCUCUCCCGUUUCUCACCUCCCAACAGUUGCUGUUCCUCAGGCCAAAGUUCACAUUCUGCACAGCCUCAGCUCCGCCUGACCUCUGAGCUCACAUGAUGGCCCUUACUGUGAACCUGGGUUUCUGGUCCAGCCAUAGCUACUUCUUUAAGCUCCUCCAGUGUGCUGAGCACAGUCUGGCCCCUGUACUGUUGUCUGCUUGAAAUGGCGUCUUCUGAUGAACACUCAUCCAUCCUUCAAGGUCUACUCUCUCAUCACAGCUUGUGACUCUUCCACUUUUUGAACUGGUGUUUCCCAUUCCCAGUUCACAGAGCCCUUUCUCAUUGAACUAUUUAUCUGAGUUCCCUCUGCCGGAACAUGAGCCAUGCCUAGAGUAGCCACCUAGUAGUGAGUGACAGCUCUGUGCUGGAUGCACAUAAAUGGUCUCCCUUAACUGCCAUGAGCCCUAAAGAAGGUUUGCUACAGCUAUUUUACAGAUGGGGAAAACUGACAGAGAGAUAUUAAUGAAUUGCCCACAUGCAAAUAUGUGCUGAGUCUUGGAUUUGCAUCUUUAUCGUGACUCCACGGAGACCCACCCUCUAAGACCAGAGCCAGUGUCCUAUUCAUCUUUUGUCUCUGCAGCGUUCAGCAUGGCACUGUCUUGGCUUACAAAAUCUGCUCUAUGCUUGCUGACUGCUGAAUGAAUGAAUGAAUGAAUAGGUAGUCACAAAGAAUGUUUAGAAUGUUUCUCAGACAGGCUGAGAAAAAACACAACGAAACAUUAUUUCCGUUUGGAAAGUUUUUUUAUUUUUGUGUUCAGUACUGAAGUAAAACAAAAAUCUGAAUAACAGCUGCACCGUUAAAAAUGAAAUUACCAAUAUAUGAACUCUAGGCAUCAUGCAUAUAUAAUUUUUUGUAGAUAACUUUUCUUCUCAUUUUCCUUCUCAUUCUCUUCAUCUUUUUCUUUUUGUUUGAGCAAAAAAAAAAAAGAAUAUAUUAACUCGUAACUGGGGAGUCUAAGAAUAAAUUCUCUUCAGCCAUUGCUGAAUCUAGGGGCUCAAAUGGUGUCUCUGGACACAGUAUCACACUCUACUCUGCACUCUUCUUUAUCAUUUUCUCCCACAGACAGACUCUCGUGUAGUUGCAACAAUGGCCAUGACUUCUAGGCUUCAUCUGCCCCUCUCAGCAGCUCUAGAGAAGAAGCUCCUCUUUUUACACAGUCCCUAAUUAAAGUCUCAGAGAUGAACAACCUGGGCUCUUGCUUAGGGCACGUGCCCAUCCUGAAUCAAUGAUCGGCCAGAGAGCUGUGAUAUUCUUUUGUUUUUUUGAGAUGGAGUCUUGCUCUGUCGCCCGGGCAGGAGUGCAAUGGCAUGAUCUCGGCUCACUGCAAGCUCUGCCUCCCGAGUUCAAGCGAUUCUCCUGCCUCAGCCUUCCGAGUAGCUGGGACUACAGGCACGUGCCACCACGCCCAGCUAAUUUUUUGUAUUUUUAUAGAGACAGGGUUUCACCAUGUUAGCCAGGAUGGCCUCGAUCUCCUGACCUCAUGAUCUGCCUGCCUCAGCCUCCCAAAGUGCUGGGAUUACAGGCGUGAGCCACCGUACCCGGCCAGGGCUGUGAUAUUCUGAUCAGCCAGCACUGAGUCACAUGGCCACUAUUAGGGUGAGGGAUGAUAGGCUUAGCUCUGACCUGAAAUUCAUGGAUUGAGGGGUGGGGACUGUUUCCCAGGGGAACACUGGGACAGCGUUACCAGGGGAAGGGGAGUGGGAUAUAGUUGGGCCAAAACAGUAAAUGUCCACGAGGCUUUUUUCCUCUGAGCAGAAAUUUCACUGUGAUGCCAGUCAGGUAUUGCUGCCGUAAGGGCCAUAGCAGGAGGGAGACUGCAAAUCUUGAUUGAGGAGAUCUUAAGAACAGAGUGAUUUACACAGCUGUGGGCAGGAUGUAGGGGAACCCAGAAAGGAUAAUGCACUACCCAGCGGCCAGCGACAGCAGGAGCUAUGAGCACCCCAGGCCUGAAGGUGUGAAGGGCUGAAAUGGUUACCAGAAGCAGGAGAGGGAAGCUUAUGGAGAGAGCAGGCUGGCGGGAGCAGGGGCUGUGAGAGAGACAGCCAGACCGUAGCGGUGUGACAGGCAGAGAGCCAGGCGAUCCAUAUCCUGUCUCCUCUCUCUUCUCCGCUCCUGACUCCUGCUGCGGCCUCCCACUGGCUGGACCCAACAGGAAAGCAGAGGAUAAGAGAAUCUGGUUGGUGCUAUCUAGAAGUCAGUGUUGGGGAGGUCACAGAACAGAAUGGAGAGGGGUAGAGUAUGCAGGGAAGAUAAAUGCAGCCCUGGCAUGGUUCUUCCAGAACAUUCUGCAAGCUCAUGGACCAGUUCAUUUGAGAAGAAAUAGAGGAGUUAGGGGAGAGAGAAGCUUCUUAAUGAAAAUAACCUUGGUAGCUAGUCUCAAGAUUAGCCCCCAGUGCUCCCCACCUGCUGGUAUCCGUUGUACAACACUUCCCACAUUUUUCUGGGGUCGUUUUGUGUAACCAAUAAAAUAUGGCAGAUGCGAUGGCAUGUUACUUCUGAAAUUGGGUUAUAAAAGGUACUGCAGACCGGGCACGGUGGCUUACGCCUGUAAUCCCAGCACUUUGGGAGGCCAAGCCUGGCGGAUCACAAGGUUAGGAGUUCAAGACCAGUCUGGCCAAUAUGGUGAAACCCUGUCUCUAUUGAAAAUACAAAAAUUAGCCGGCAUGGUGGCACACGCCUGUAGUCCCAGCUAGUCGGGAGGCUGAGGCAGAAGAAUCGCUUGAACCCGGGAGGCGGAGGUUACAAUGAGCUGAGAUAGCACCACUGCACUCCAGUCUGGGCAACAGAGCGACACUCCGUCUCCAAAAAAAAAAGAUACUGCAGCUUCUAUCUUGGUUGCUCACUUGCUAUCUUGGGUCCCUCCCUCUGGGGAAAGCCAGUUGCCAUCUCCCAAGGAUCCCUAUGGACAGACCCAUUUGGCAAGGAACAGCCACCAGCUAGCUGCAUGAGCGAGCCAUGUUGGAAGUGGGUCCUCCAGCUGCAGUCAAGCUUCCAGAUGACCACUGCCCUGGGAAACGACUGCAACCUCAUGAGAGACCCUGAGCCGGAACCACCCCACAAAGUCACUCUUGAUUUCCUAAGUCUCAGAAACUAUAAAAUAUAAAUGUGUGUUGUUUUAAAAUCCUAGGUUUUGAGGUAAUUUAUUAUACAGCAAUAGAAAACUAAUACAAUAGUCUUGCUACCAGCACCUUAAUCUCCCACAUCCAAGUUAAAAUUCAUCCAACACUCAAUCUCCCAGCUAUCCUGACUGCUCCUAUACAGGUAUCUCUCCCACUAUAUAUAUAUCAAGUGCUAUUAGUGGCUAUUAUUUGUUGGGUUACACAAAGCCAGAAAUCAUCUACAUCUACUCUCUUUUCUUCUGGUUUUGAAUAGCAAAAUGCAACAGGGAGAUGUUCUCAGAUAGAGGGAGAACAACAAAAAGAAGGGUCCAUGCUGAACAAACUUGUUUGCUUUGAAAUCGGAAGUUCUAGAGGAGGUAUUCUGACAGUGGCCAGGAAAACCUCCUGCCCGCAGAAUUUUGUCUAAUCCACCCCAGACAGAGUUAUCCAACAGCCUGGUAUGGUGCAGACCAGGGGCUCUCGAAAGGUGGGCUCCAGGCAGCAGCACCAGUAGCACCUGGGAAAUUGUUGGAAAUGCAAAUUCUUGGGCUCCACCCCAGAUCAACUUAAUCGGACUCUCUGGGAGUAGGGCCCAUCAAUCUGUGUUUAACAAGUCCUCCAGGUGAUUCCGAUCCUAAUCAAGUGUGAGCCCACUGUCUAAUGCGGUGCAUACCAAAGCAGGUGCACGGGUCUUAAUCAUCACCUCAGUCCUCUGAAACAGGCAAGUGUGUCCAUUUUACAGAAGAAGGAACUAAGGCCUGGAAGGCAAGUCCUUGCCUGAGACUAAACAGAAUCCCAGCAACAUAGGACGAGGCUGGAAUUCCCACACCUGGACUAAUGCACAGCCAGUGUUUCAACGUCGCCAACCCAGAAAUGUUUUCUCUCCCUGUCAUGCUAAUUUUCAGCCCUUUCUGGGUGACUUGUUCAUCAUCCAAAUAUAUUAUUUUUGUUUUGUUUGACUAAAGGCAAUUAUAUUUACAUUUUCUCUAAGUACUGGAAUGUAAUGGUUGAAAUUCCUAUUCAGUGAUCUGGAAGAACUCUAAUGUUCUAAAGUGAUUCUUUGAUAAUUAAAGAAAGAUGUAAUUAUGUAUAA